AUGGAUCUGCCCAUGAAUCUGCACACCGACAACUUCUUUCAACUUCUUCUCUUCUGGAUCAAUAAGAAUGAGUAUUUUCUGAUUUGUCACUGUUCUAAAUGCAUCGACCUUCAUCAUGCCAAGGAAAAUGGCGGGCAGCAGAGGGAUGGAAAGAAAGAUAUGCCUGAAAGGGGAAGUGCUCAAUGGGGAAUGGGUGGGCCACGGGUGGUGAGCUGCGAGGAGCAGCUCCUCCAUUGUUCGCGGGCUCCGGGCCCCGCCGUCCCCGCCUCCCCCUGGACCCCGCAGCGGGGCGGCGCCCGGCCUCGCCGCCCGGGGCCCGUGAGCUCGCGCACUCACCAGCUGGGCGCCCUCAGCGCGGCCCCGGCCUCCAAAAUCCCGGCAGCAACGACGGGGGCCCCGGCGCCAUGUUCCCCUGCUCCUAGUCCAGCGGCGGCUGAGGCGGCGGCGGCGGCUCCGGCGGCGGGGGGCCGGGCGGACCCUCCCUCGCGGCGGCGGCACCUCCUUCCUGCGACGGCCGCUCCCGCGCGCGCGCCCCCUCGCUACUGCGCGUGCGCGGCGCGUGGACCGUUGCAGGGGUAUAACGGCCCCUGGGCGCGCGCCGCGAAGGGACAACCAGCGAGGCAGUGGGAAGAGGUCAGAGCGCGUGCGCACCCGAGGGGCUUACUGCCACAGCCGCUGCCUGAGGUUAGGAACGGCCGCGGACGGUGCAGUGCGCGUGCGCCCCCGAAAAUGCCGCUAUUGCGGCGGCCGCCGUCGCGACUGAGCGCGAGGCGACUUGCAAACGAGCAGAGGGAGCGGGAUGGGCGAGCGCGCGUGCGCGGGGGGCUGCCAGCCGGCGCAGCUGCUGGCGCAGGGCGGAGGGAGUGGUCCGCAGGAGCUGCGCGCGCGUCUCAAGCAGCCGAUCUACUGCCUCGCGCUGGCUCCUGGAGAAAGCCGAAGGAGAGAGGCAUGGCCCGGUUUUGGGGGUGGGGGGCGAAGGGCGCGAUCCCGCUCGCGCGGGACCUGACCAGCCAAUGGGAAGCAAUGGGAGGUGGGUUUGCCGCGCGAGCCGCAGCCGCCGGGAUAACGGAGGAGGCCAGAAGGAGCGACGUAACGUGGGGCGGUGGGGCGGGGCUGAGAAGGAGGGAGCGCACCAGAGAGGGAGUUGAUUGGAGGAUAUGAGGAGGCGUGGCCCGCCUCAGCCCAAUCCGAGCCCCGCAAUUCGUCGUCCCGGAAGAAGAGGCGGGGCUGGAGAGCGCGUGCUCUUUCUCCUGGCUGUGAAGAAAAUCUGCAGCCAACGCGCGCGUCCAUGCAACUUGUUUUUGGUUCUGUGAACGACUGAUCCCCAGGAGAGGGAAGACGGCCUGGUCCUGUGUGCAGCCCAAGCCUGUCACUUAGCAUUGUGCAAAUGGCUACAAAUCGAAUGUCAAUUAGGGCGCCUGAAGGGAAAAGAGUAGUGAUGGGAGAGGGCACCGCUGUAACCCUUGACUCCUCUGAACUGAGGAGGUGUUCCUCUGGGACUCCUCCGGAAGUACAGAUCGUGGAAGAUGAGCUUCCCGGGCGCCGAGCCAAUAUUUGUGGAAUGCAUGAAGAAAGGCUGUUUCCUAUUACAUUUGGCAUUUCUGCCAUCAGUCUCUUCAUCUAUAAAAUGGGAUAAUAAUCGUACCUCUCUCGUAGGGCUGCUGUGAAAAUUAAAUAGAUUAUAUUUUGCAAAGCUCUUGAAAUCAUGCAUUGCAUACAUAGUAAGCGCUCUGUAAGCGUUGAUAAAUAAAAUUACAGGGGCUUGUUUAUUCCAUUAAUAAAGAUUUUUAUAUUAAA